GUCCCUACAACAUCCAUUUUAUCCACAGCUGAUACACAACUAAUGAUUCAACUAGGUCAUUUAUUUAUAUUUUAAAUUGCCUUCGAUGCUCUGUCAGAAGCCUACUUAACACUGAAUAAUCUAAAGCCCUGGUUCUUCUAUAGAUCUGAUAAGUAAAAGUGUUUUACAAAUGAGUUCUACUGAAAUAUUUUAAAUGUUUGCCCUUCCCACUCCCAUUUCCUAAUCCCUAUUCCAUGAAGCUUAGGUCAAUACAACAGUUUACAUAUGUUAACAUUUACAGAAGAAGAAUUCAAACAGAGGUGAAAUGAAAGAGACUGAUCUUUGAGCACUUUCCCAUGAAAAUGUUGUUAUAUAUCCUUUGUGAUAUAAAAUUUUAAAUCAUAGAAUUAUAAAUAUUUAUAAGGAACACAGUCAUAUUUUAAUUAAAAAGAAAGGACCAAAAGAAGUUAAAUGCCUUUCCUUUGUCUGUAUGACUGUAUUGUAAUAAAUUAGUCUCUCUGGAUGAAUAUCAGCAAAACUAACUUUCUAUGUAUUUCUUUUGAGUUUCAAACAGGAAACUUUAUCUGGGAAUACUUUAACAGUUCAUCUCUGGAAAUUUACAAGAGCUCUACAACUGUCCAUCGAAACUUCACUAUAAUGUGCUUAAGAGCCCUUAUAUGUGAUAUAAUUUUUAUAUGUUUUCAUCAGUAAGGAUAUCUUUAUGGACAAAUUCCAAAUGACUAAACAUGUAUGUGUAUGUGUGUUUCACACAUUGUCAGCAUAAAGUAAGUUCUUACUGUUAUCGUUAGACUUACACAGAUGAAUAGAUGGACAAAUAGGUAGGUAUGUCUGUUCAGAAUGAUAUUAUCUUGGUUGGAUUGCCAUUAGUAUCAGAAAAGAAAGUGUUCUUUUCAAUACCUAUGAUUUAAGGAACAUUUUGCUAUAAGCUCUAAUAUUUCAUAAUUUCCAUUCAAAACAAUAUACCAAAUGAGAAGGAUGGAAAGAAUAGUCAAGGCUUCUGCCUAUGAAUCAAGACAAUGGAUGUGGGCAAUAAGUCUACCAUGUCUGAAUUUGUUUUGCUGGGGCUCUCUAAUUCCUGGGAACUACAGAUGUUUUUCUUUAUGGUGUUUUCAUUGCUUUAUGUGGCAACAAUGGUGGGUAACAGCCUCAUAGUCAUCACAGUUAUAGUGGACCCUCACCUACACUCUCCUAUGUAUUUCCUGCUUACCAAUCUUUCAAUCAUUGAUAUGUCUCUUGCUUCUUUCGCCACCCCAAAGAUGAUUACAGAUUACCUAACAGGUCACAAAACCAUCUCUUUUGAUGGCUGCCUUACCCAGAUAUUCUUUCUCCACCUUUUCACUGGAACUGAGAUCAUCUUACUCAUGGCCAUGUCCUUUGAUAGGUAUAUUGCAAUAUGCAAGCCCCUGCACUAUGCUUCUGUCAUUAGUCCCCAGGUGUGUGUUGCUCUCGUGGUGGCUUCCUGGAUUAUGGGAGUUAUGCAUUCAAUGAGUCAGGUCAUAUUUGCCCUCACGUUACCAUUCUGUGGUCCCUAUGAGGUAGACAGCUUUUUCUGUGACCUUCCUGUGGUGUUCCAGUUGGCUUGUGUGGAUACUUAUGUUCUGGGCCUCUUUAUGAUCUCAACAAGUGGCAUAAUUGCGUUGUCCUGUUUUAUUGUUUUAUUUAAUUCAUAUGUUAUUGUCCUGGUUACUGUGAAGCAUCAUUCUUCCAGAGGAUCAUCUAAGGCCCUUUCUACUUGUACAGCUCAUUUCAUUGUUGUCUUCUUGUUCUUUGGGCCAUGCAUCUUCAUCUACAUGUGGCCACUAAGCAGCUUUCUCACAGACAAGAUUCUGUCUGUGUUUUAUACCAUCUUUACUCCCACUCUGAACCCAAUAAUCUAUACUUUGAGGAAUCAAGAAGUAAAGAUAGCCAUGAGGAAACUGAAAAAUAGGUUUCUAAAUUUUAAUAAGGCAAUGCCUUCAUAGUUUUUGUGACACAGAACAUUAGACACAAUGCUGUGUUAGGCUUUUCUUUCUAGAGGGUUCUUACCAAAUUGUAAUUGCCAAGAAUUUGUGAGGGCUCAAGUUCAGUGCAUUUUGAAACUAUUCUCAUGAAUGUGAAUGUGUUCAAAAUACAUUUGAAAUUUCAGAAAAGCAAGUUAAAAGAAAUAAAGACUAUAAAAAUGUCAGGAGUGACAGUUCCAGUUAGGACAUUCAAUAUCAAUAAUCAAUUUAUUGGAAAAGAGGACCAAGGAAUGAGGAGAAGAAAUAUAGAUUAAAGCAGAACUAGGAGAUAAUGACAAUUACCCACAGUGAGCAACUGAGUCACUUAGUGAGAUGCUCCUAAAGUAUGACAAGCUAGCAAGAUUCCUAUAAUCCUUAGGAACUCCAUACUGCUGUAGGAUCUUAGCCUCUGACAGAGAAGCAAUGAUUUUCCACAUACGUUCCCAAGCCACUCCUACUUAACAUUUAAACCAAUUUGUGAUCUCUUCUAUUAAAGAAAACUCUAGAUAUAUUUUAUUUCGAAUGUUAAUGACGUCCAUAAAAUUGCCGUAAGUGUAGCAAUCUUUACCAACCACUUUUAGUUCAUCAUCAAAGCAAUACAGUCAUGAUAUUUCUUUCUGAUAAUGCGGAAUGAGUAGGGAGGCUGGAGAAUUCUGCAAAUCAGAAAAUAUGAAAUGAGUUGCAGAUCAGUACACUUUGUUUUGUGCAGACACGAUGGUUGCUUAGUUCCUAAGAAGUUAAAACUAGAAUUGAGAGACACAGUUUAUAACAGUUGAAUUUAUGGGGAGUCCAUGCUUUCAUUUUAAAGUGUUAUAUUGCUUUCCAUUUUGGUUAUUUUUUUCUUGAAAUAUUUGGAUGUAAAAAUAAUGAAUCUGCAUUUAGUAAUACAUUGUCAAUGUAAUAAGUAUGUUUUUGUACACAAAUAGGUUUUAUUACUGUUAUAAAUAAAUCUGGUAGGUUCAAUAUUAGCUUUAAUGUAUACAAAGUAUUACUACCACCUGCUGGUACUAACUGGAAUUGCAAGUAUUGAAAGAGGAAAAAUAAUUGUGUAUACCCUACUUUGCAAAUCAUCUUUAAAUGAUGGCAAACAUUCAUGAGUUAACUCUUAUUUAGAAUUUUCUAAAUGAUAUUGAUAAAAUAUAGUGUCUUAUAUAUGAUCCAACAUGUAUCCACAAAGGGAAAGAUAUGUUGCAACCACAGUAUUUGAUAAUAUCAAGUUGUUAUUUUCUGGUAUGAUUGAGUAAAUGGAGAAAACAAAUGAAAUGCAUUAAUUAUCAUUUAUGAAAGAUAAUUAAAACAGAAAAUCCUUAGAUGUUCAUAUUAAACCAAGUUAUAAAAGGAAUUUAUUUUUUCUUCAUCAGUUUGUGUUUUAUUUCUUCAUUAAUGUACUAAGCAAAUAAGGAAAAAACUUACAGCUUGAAAGUCUGUGAUACUGUGUUUAAAGCCUGAGCAGUUUUGAAAUUAUUAGAUAAUAACGUCUACAGUAUUAACAUAAAAUAAAACAUGCUUCUGUAAGCACAAGAUUAGCAUAAUUCUAUUUUAAAUAGGGAUACAAAUAGGCCAAUUUAGGUUUUGAGUGUGAACUUUCUCUUGGUUGCAGUUAUAUGUACAAAUAUGUUCAUAUUCAAGGACUUCGUUUAUGUAGAAUGUUUUAGCUGGUGCUUAAAAAUGCUAGAAAUAAUUCUUUUACUUGACAUAUUUCUUUGUCCAGGGAAUAUUUUCAAAACUGUGCUGCUUUUUGCAAUAUAAAACUGUGGAAUCUUUUGGAAGAGACGCUAUUGAUUUUCUGUGCUUUUGUGGAGAAUUCUAAAACUCAAGAACAUUUGCCAAAAUACCCUCAAAGGUGUAGCUGAUCAGCAGACAACUCUAUAAGGCAAGUCAAUAAUGAGAUUAAGUAGUUGGAUUGAUAGUAAAAUUCUGUGGCUGAUAAUAAAAAGGAUUACAGAAAGCCUUUGGAGGGCUUACAUAUAUAAAUGGAACUAUCACAUUUCUCGGUGGCUUAGUGUGAGGAGUCAAUAUUCAUGGUACCUCUGCAUGUUAUAUAAACACUUAAAAAUCUUAGUUAGGACUUUAGGACUCAUGGUGGUUGGUUUUAUCGAUAUAUCUCUUAGACAAGAUGCUGACACUCUUUCACCAAGGAUAACUGCAGUGACAUGGCCAUGGACUCGUUAAGCAAUAGUAAGGAUGGUGCCAGCUGCCACCAGAGUUUCCAGAGACAGAGAUAAUGUUCUGCAGAGAAUACAAGAUAAGCAGGCAAGUAUAAUUUUAAGUGAUCUGCACUAUCUGCAAUAACACAACUGAGGGAGUUCUGGAGCAUUUAUAAGAAGAGUGUGUUGACAAGCAACUUCAUCUUCCUCUACGUGUUUAGGAAGCUGUGAAGCUUGACAACAAUUGAAUGCAGAUGGAAAAACUGUUAAAAAUCAGGUAUAGAUAAAAACAGAUAAAGUGUAAAUUUUAAUAUGUGAAGGAACUGGAUAUAUGUAAUAGCAAUAAAAACUACAAAUUAUGUUUGUUUCUAAAAAUGCUUAAGAAAACUUUUAGAAUACUAUAUGGUAUAAUGAUGGUGGAUUUACCAUAAAGCUUGUAAAGCUUAGGUUUUAUAACUCCUCCUUUGCAUGGAUUUCCUCGAAGGCCCUAGAAUGGAAACUAACAACCUUUUAUUAGUUAUUUCGAUUUUUUUUUCCUGAAACAGGUGUCCUCAAACUGUAUAAGCUUUAAGCCUAGCUUGUCCAACCCAUGACCUGCAGGUUGCAUGCGGCUCAGGAGAUGGCUUUAAAUUCAGCCCAACACAAAUUCAUAAGCUUUCUUGAAACAUUAUAAGAUUUUCUUGUGAUUUUUUUGUAAAGCUCAUCAGCUAUCUUUAGUAUCAGUGUAUUUUAUGUGUGGCCCAACACAAUUCUUCUUCCAAUGUGGCCCAGAGAAGCCAAAACUUUGGACACCCCUGCAUUAAAAGGCUCUGCAGAAUCUGAAGUCUAAUGUGUAGUUUUAAAAGUCUUAGACUCUGGUAUCUUUUUUUUUUUUAAACAGUGUUUAAUACUACUUCUACUACUAGUGGUGUAAACUUAAGCUAAGUACUUAAUACCUCUUAGCCUCAGUUUCUACAUAUGUUAAAGGAGAUAAUAGUGGUCUCUACACCACAGAGUUAUUUGAGGCAUAAAAGAAGCAAAUAAUAUGAAGCAUAUGGUUGUCAAUAAAUGUUAGUCAUUGUAUCAUUCUGGGUGAUAACCUCUGGAUAUCUUUGUUUAUGGGACUUGAUAGUCUCUUGAGCUAACACUUGACUUGUUUAAUUUAAAAGGUAAAUUUUCAUUUAUAUGUUUUAAAUAUUCAUGUCUGUAUAUGUGUGUCAGUAUUAAUUUGAAAAAUUAAAAGUAACUUCCACUAGAAAAUUACACUGGUUCUUACAUUAAUUAAAGCUUCUGGAAACUUGUUUUUCUGUCUGUUCACAACUGUCAUUAAUCAAGAGAAGUAUCAAGUUGUUGCUUAAUCAUUAUGCUAUUGCUUCUUUACAAUGAAUAAAUAUUAAAUUGGUUUAUUGAUUUUAGGAUGAAUUCACAUUACAAUUGUUGUCAGAAUAAGAAUGAUGUUUGACUCAUAUUAUUAAGGUGAAGAGAUAGGCAGAUGGAUAGAUUAGUAGAUAGAUGAAGUUUUGUAUUAUAUGAGCUGUCUUAUGUGAAGUAUUUUUCUGCAUUGAUAAGGGUUUAGGAUAAUGUGAUCACUGGAUUAUGCUGCUAUAUAGAAGUUCUUGGUAAAAUGCUGUUAUUUGUGCAUAUCCAGACUCCUUAUGAAAGUAUUUUCAAAUUUAAAAAACUACCAGUGAAUCUAUUCUCUACAUGUGAGUUUUUAAACAACUCAGUUAUAGCAAAAUUUGUUGAGAGAGUUGGAGUAAUCCUCCUAUUUCCCUAUUCUUUCCCUGAUAUUAUUUUGCAUGAUUUUUGGAUGUAUAUGUCAAUUGAAAAACGGGGAGAAGAAAACAGCCAGGGAAAUCUAAUUCAUGUGAACUUCUUGCAUGUACUCUCAGAUGCCAAUGAAAUCCGCUAAGCAACUUGAUAGUUUUUUGGUUUAUAAGUUUCUGUUGUGCUUUGUUGUUUGGAAUUAUUUUUAAUGCUCUUGGUUACACCAUGAGGUAAAUAUGCACAAAUUAUUCUGGAGCGUGUAGGACCAACACUCAAAUGAGACUGGAAAUGUGACUGGGAUCAUUGAUUCAUGUAUUCUGUCUCUAUUGUUGCUAAUAUAACUCAAUUGACAUGUUAUUUUUUCUCUUUGAUUUUUGUAAAACAAACAAAUAAAUUCCAAUAUCUAGUAUGCACUAAAAUACUAUAGUUUCAUUUUUAUUUUUUACUCUGAUAAUUUACACUGCCAAUAUAAGGAGAUGAAUACCUAUUUUUUAAAUUAAAAAAUGUUCUCGGGCUGGAGGCUCCAGGUUUUUUUCCCCCAUUAGCCUUUUUAUGACUACUAAAUGCAAGACCACUGUUAAUUCGCCUUUUUUCUUUGUGUUUUAACUGUACUAGGAAUCUGAAGCCAUCAACAAAAGCCAGAUUUUUCUCCCUUUGCUCACUUGCCACCUGUUAAAGAAAAUUUAAAGGAGAGAUUUUUUUUUUUAGUUUGAGACUAGAAAUAGCAAUUUAAUUAGUAAUUUGUUUUUAUAUAAUAAUAUAUUUAUAUCAAUUUUUUCUUCUUGUUUGAGUGUACUUAUAUUGGUUGUCCUACAGUUAAGAAAACGGAAACCAUUGGGUAAAUUAAGCAGAUUUAAUACAAUGUAUUAAAUGCUUGUGAAUAAUUCAAAGACUUACAGGAACAUGCAUUGGAGGCUGCAACUGGAGCUAUUGUGUUCCAGAGCACAUUACCCCAGUAAUGUGAUGUAAGGGCAAAAGGCAAAAAGCCUUGGUGUCAUUGCCACUCCUUCAUCACCCUCAGCACUCUUGAAGGUGGUGAAUAGUCACUGGACACAGGUAUGGCUGCCACAGUUGCUUUCCCUCACAUCUCAUCAUCAUCUUGCUCACCAGCGGCAAUUAUAUCAGUAGAUCCCUCUGCCUCACUUGUGCUUUCUAAAGCUCAUUUGGUGCAUCUAAUUGGUGGAAUCUAUUUUGCACAGAGAAACUUGGCUUCAAAAAUCAAUUUGUAGAUUUCAAGAUUCUUAUGCAACAGAAAACAUGCUAAUAGAGGGUGGAUUGGAGGGAGACUCCGUCAAUCAAUCAAUAUCCAUUACUUUAAUUUUUUUAUUAUAACCUUUUUAUUGCAGUGUAAAAGCAAGGUAAAGAAAAAUACACAAACAUGUUUAGCUUAAUGAAAUAUUACAAGGCAAACACCAUUAUAAUCACAUUUCAAGUCACAAAAUAGAACUUCGCCAGCCACCCCUGAAGUCCUCAAGUUUGUUCAUCUCGAUGACAACUCUCUCCUCCAAAAUUAACCAUUACCCUGACUUAAUAAAUUAUUUGCAUUUCUUUUCAGUUUCAUGAAUACAUAUAUACUCAAAUAUACAUCCAUACACACUCAAACUUGGCCUCACCAACUUUGUUUCCUUUUCUUGUAGCCUACAAGUCUCACUAUCACUAUCUCUUCAAUUUCUGUAUAAUUUAUCUUUCUUUUUCUUUUUUUUUUCUUUUUUUUUUUUUUUUGAGACGGAGUCUUGCUCUGUCGCCCAGGCUGGAGUGCAGUAGCGUGAUCUCCGCUCAUUGCAAACUCUGCCUUCCGGAUUCACGCCAUUCUCCUGCCUCAGCCUCCUGAGUAGCUGGGACUACAGGCGCCCGCCACCACGCCCAGCUAAUUUUUUGUAUUUUUAGUAGAGAAGGGGUUAUAAUUUAUCUUUUGAAAAACCUGAGUUAUUUACCAUCUAGGGUCUCCCAGAGUCUGAAAUAUGCUGAUUGCAUGCUCAUGGUACAGUUCAACAUGGACUUCUGUCACUGCAUUUUCUGCAAAUUGCCUAUCCAGCAGCUUAAUCAUAUUUAGUUUGAUACUUUUUGCAAGACAAAUGACAGAUGAUGUUAUAUUUUUUCAUCCAAAAGAUCUUGAUGUCUUGCUUUAUCUCUUUGGGAAUGAUAGUGCUGUUGUUGCUGUAGUAGUUGAUAUCUCUAACCAUUUUUGUUGGCUGAAGCUUAUUCUCUACUAUAUUCCUCAGGAAGUCUUCUUGAAGACCCUAUUCUCUGAAUUCUGGCGUGUUGGCAAGUUUCUUUGAAACAUUUAUGUACUGUAAUUUCAUUGGCUAUUCCUUUAUUUUCUUGAUUAUCUUAAAUUGAAAUAAUGACUCUCUUUGUAAGCACUUUGUCUGGAGUCUGCAAAGCCUGUAUUUUUCUUCACUCACCCUAGCAUACCAUAUAAUUAGAAGUUUGGAACUGAUCUUUUAAUUUUUGGAGGGAGGUAUUAAUAAUCCUUCUGAUAUUUAUAUUAGUAGUUAAAUAAUUAAAUAGUAGUUAAAGUAAUUAAAUAGGACUCUAUUGCACUCAAGAGAUUUUAAAACGUUUAAAUUUCUAAAUUUCCUUUAAGUAUAUUAAAAUGUACCUAAAUAAAAUUGUUCUUCAAGAGUAACAUGUAAUUGAAUCAUCAACAUCUUUAUAUAACUUUUCCAAUUUUUUAAAGAAAGAUACCUCUCUUGCAGCUCAAUUGCUUUUUAAAUAAAAUAAAUUUGAAUCCCUGUUUGUACCUGGAGACCGUUUUGAUCUGCCCUCCUCACCUCACAUUUCACACAUGGAGAAAAAAAGUCUGCAC